GCGAGUGGCGGGCCGACUGUGUAGUCCGCUCCGGCAGCGCGCUCUGCCCGGCUUCCUCAGUCUCCUCGCCGGGAGCGUCCGGGAGCAGCUCCGAGGCCGCGGCGAAACCAGGUGGAGUCCGAGGUUCGGAGGAGUAUCAGAGGUUAGGGGAAGGCCGGAGAAUGGGCUGGGAGGCUGCGUUUCGGAGCUUAGGGUUCUGUCCCUGCGAUCGCCGCGUCUCCCUCCCUUGGUGGGCGCGGCUCCCGGGAAGCGGCUCGUCUCGUCUCCCCUCACAGGCCGGGUUCCCGUUCUGGACCUUCGCCCUCGGAACACAGUGCUGUUGGCCGGGACUCCUUCCCGAGGUGGACGGCUCCCUGUUCUUAUUCCUGGCUCUGCCAGAACUGUAGGAAGUGCUCAGUACACUUUAGGGCAUGCAUGGCACUCCCUGGGAGACAGUGCUUUAGGGCCAGAGGAAAGAUCUUCCCUGAAGGCAAACGCCCGCGGAGCCCACAAGUCCGGGCCGCACUGAACAAGUCAGGAUGUUGCCAUCGGCAAUUCUGCAGAAGGCAGUAACCCAUCUGAGAGAAAGAGCCGCUGUCAUAAGGGAGCAGGGAUUGGAUCAAGUCAUUGCAUCUAGAGUACGGGGGAACGAAGAAAUCAUGGAGAGAGUUUGCCCCAGGAGAGAGGCGAGCGUUAUGUAACCUAGGAUCUGGGGUGGGUAACAGUCUGUGCAGUGUCAAUGUGAGAGGAGAAAACACCCAACGUGAGGGAAUGGUCAGGUAAGAAAGGACCAGAAGUUCCGGUUCUACCAUAGCAAGGACCUAAGUUGCUAAUUUAGGUUCUUUAAUGCAGACCUGGUCUUUCAGAACUUCUUUCUCUUCCCUAGCCUUGUCAUUUCAGCAUUCUGGCCUUCCCUAUGAGGAGGAAGAUCAACGAAGUCACAGGGCCCUUCUAGCCCAAUCCAGAGCUGUACCAUGGCAGAGACAAGAGAAGAGGAGACAGUGUCAGCAGAAGCCUCAGGGUUCUCAGACUUGAGUGACUCAGAGUUCCUGGAGUUUCUGGACCUAGAAGAUGCCCAAGAGUCAAAGGCUUUAGUUAACAUGCCUGGCCCAUCUUCUGAAUCCCUUGGGAAGGAUGACAAACCCAUAAGCUUACAAAACUGGAAAAGAGGAUUGGAUAUAUUAUCACCCAUGGAGAGAUUCCACCUUAAAUAUUUAUAUGUCACUGACCUGGCUACUCAGAACUGGUGUGAACUGCAAACAGCAUAUGGGAAGGAGCUUCCUGGUUUCUUGGCACCUGAGAAGGCAGCUGUGUUGGACACUGGUGCCAGCAUACACCUAGCUAGAGAACUAGAACUUCAUGAUCUUGUGACUGUCCCAGUCACCACUAAAGAAGAUGCUUGGGCAAUUAAGUUUCUGAACAUACUUUUGCUGAUUCCUACCCUGCAGUCAGAAGGGCACAUCAGAGAGUUUCCAGUGUUUGGGGAAGGGGAGGGUGUACUUCUUGUUGGAGUGAUUGAUGAGCUGCACUAUACAGCCAAGGGGGAACUGGAGCUGGCGGAACUCAAGACACGCAGGCGCCCUAUGCUCCCUCUGGAAGCUCAGAAGAAGAAAGACUGUUUUCAAGUCAGCCUAUACAAAUAUAUCUUUGAUGCCAUGGUACAAGGAAAAGUGACCCCUGCUAGCCUAAUCCACCACACAAAGUUGUGUCUAGAAAAGCCACUGGGGCCAUCAGUGCUGAGGCAUGCCCAGCAGGGAGGCUUCUCUGUGAAGUCUUUGGGUGACCUCAUGGAACUUGUCUUCUUGUCUCUAACACUGUCAGACCUCCCAGUUAUUGAUAUCUUGAAGAUUGAGUAUAUCCACCAAGAGACUGCCACUGUGCUGGGUACUGAGAUUGUAGCCUUCAAAGAGAAGGAGGUGAGAGCCAAGGUGCAGCAUUAUAUGGCCUACUGGAUGGGCCACCGAGAGCCCCAGGGAGUUGACGUGGAGGAGGCUUGGAAGUGCCGGACGUGUACCUAUGCAGACAUUUGUGAGUGGAGAAAGGGCAGUGGAGUGCUCAGCUCUACACUGGCGCCCCAAGUCAAAAAAGCCAAAUGAAUAGAAGGUAUGCUUUCAAGAAUGUUGAUCCUUCCUGCUCCUGUUGUACCUAAGCAAAAGAGGACCAGUCUCUGAGCUUGGCUUUUAUGGAGAGUGUUCUUAUUUUGGUUCUUUUUUUUAUUUCCACAACCUCUAACCACAUUCAGUCCAGGACCAAGGCUCAGGGAUGAGUGGGAGAGAUGGGUUAUACUGUCCCUGGAGCUUCAUCAUGAUUGCCUGAGAAGACAGAUGCUCAUCAUGGCUGGAAUGAAGGUAUCCUUCAGUAAACUUUGCUUUCCUAAGAAAAUUCUUCAGUUUCUGAUAAGUCAUCCCUAUUUUUAUCUUGAUCAAGGCUUUCUACAGUUACAUAAUAAAAUGAAAUGCUGUCCAGGA